AGUCACUUAAACCAUCGUAGACAAAGCACAUGUGAAGGUGUGAUUAAGGAGCACUGUCCCAUUGGUGCCUGGGGACAGAUGAUUUGCCUGGUGGGCCUCUUAUAUCCCCCGAUGUCAUUUAUAUCACACCAGCUAAUGAUGGGAUAUGGCAGUGAGUAUUACCGACGACUUUCUUUAAGUUGUAUAAUUAUAAUAUUUCAGAUAUACUAUAUCAGAGGAAAAGAUGUGUUUUCUCUUGCUUAGCCGAGCCUUCCUAUUAGGCUUAUGGUCAUUUCAAGGAAAACGAUGAUCCAGGGCUGUAACAUUGAUGAUGUCCCUUGCCUCUCUCUAACCUGGAUUUGUUACAGAUAUGCUGAUGACUGAGACCCAUGAUGCAGAUCGUGAUUUCUGUAGCAUUUUGCUAGCAGAGGAUUUGACAUUGCCUUGAGACUUAAUCAUUUUGGAGAAUGUUCUCUCAAUUGGCAGCAGAAGGUUUGCAGCUCCAGAGGCUGCAGUGGAGGCUUUUGGAUUAUUAAAAGUUGAGACCUAAUCACAAAUUGAGGCAGUGCAGCAAAUCCACUCCUUCCUAUUAUUCUUGUGCAUUAGGAGCCACUUAAGCUCCACCUAAUGAAGAGUCUUCAUUCUUUGCAUUGUAAUACUCCUUUAAAGAUGCUCAGAGAGCCUCACAAAUCCUGCCUCUUUCUACUUCCCAGCACAGCGGGCAGAGAGAGCAAACUCUGCCACAGGGUCCUGGCACCAACGCAGCCCCCUCUAUCCUGCCAGGUGCUUCUUCUCUUUAUUUGUGUCCUCUGACAUCCUCUCAUUCUUCUCCCUUCCUUUCCCAUAUGUCAUCUCCCCAUGACAAACAAGGGUAGUUUCUUCUGGGUAGAAACUAGGCGUUUUCAUAUAAUGGAGGCUAUGUCUGUGUUGAUGCAGAGAAAAACACAAAAGCCCUGUAAAAUAUUUAAACCUGAGCCAAUGUGAGUGACCAUGGCCCAGGCUUAUGGUCUUAGGAAGUCCUGAGAACGUGUGCCCGAGGCAACUGGGUCACAGGUUGGUUUUACACACUUUAGGGAGACAGGCAUUGUAGAUAAAAUCAUUAAUCAAUACAUGAAAGGUGUGCAUUGGUUUAGCCUAAAGUGGUGGGAUAUUUUGAAAUGCGGGUUUAUAAGUCGUAGGUACAUUCAAAGAUUUUCUGAUUGGCAGUUGGUUGAAAGAGUUAAGCUUUGUCUCAAGGCUUGAAGUCAAUAGAAAUAAAUGCUUGAGUUAAGAGGGGUUGUGGAAGCCAAGAUUCUUGUUAUAGAGAUGACGCCUCAUAGGUAGUGUCCUUCAGAGAGGAUAGAUGGUACAUGUCUCUUUUGGGAACUUAAAGGUGUUACACUCACAUUUAAUCUCUCCUAGGUCCAGGAAAGGCCUAGAAGGGGAAAGGUAGGCUGCAUUAAUGGAGAUGCUCUACCAAUGCAAAUUUCCCCCACAAAAGACAGCUUUGCAUGGCCAUUUCAACAUAUGUCAAAGAAAUAUAUUUUGGGGUAAAAUAUUUUGAUUUCCUUCAGGGUCUUCUAACUGUCACGUGAUGCUAUACCAGAGUCAGGUUGGAAUUUGGCAUCUUAUCGCCACAAAGAGUUUGGUCAGCUUAUGAUGUCUAUGUUAAUAUUAAUCCUGGUCAGUUGUGUCCACAUAUCAAAGGGAGAGGGAAUAUAUGGAGGCCUGUCUGACCUCCCUUCCAGUCAUGACUGGAAAUUCAGUUUUUCAUGUUUCUCUGGGGUCCAUCUGGCCAUGAGGGGGUCUGUUGGGUCAGUUGAGGCGCUUAGGAAUUUAUUUUCAGUUUACAUCUGUGUCAACCUUAAAUAAUGAGGUUCAGGAAAUAUGAUUAAGUACAGAGUUUAUUUGAGCGCAAAGCUUGAGGCUGGCCACCUGGGAAAGCACCAACUGCAGAUGAAUGGGGUCAGUGUUUCCAAAACGGAGAAGUUAAAGUUUCGAUUAUAUAGGCAGAGUCAGAGAAGUUCCAGCAGAAUCACAGCAUUUUCCAUACAAGACCAGGUAUAUAUGCCACAGCUGUUUGAUUGGUUACAGAUUGUUCCAUUUUAAGCAAGAAUACUUUAUUAUUCCAUGAGGAGGUGCAGUGAUCUGAGAGGGUCUUAUCUCUGGCGCUGCUUGGUCUUUCUAAUUAUUUGCAGGAACAAAAAGGCAGAAGUUGCAGCUGUCUGACGCAGGCUACAUAGCCACAUUCCUCCCAAGGCUCAAGAUAAUUUUGAGUUCCAAUAGCUUUAAGUUUGAAUUAUUUUAAUUUUGAAUUAUUUAAUUUUACAUCUGAUAAUUUGAAUCCUGCCAUGAAAUUUCCCAAGUUCACUUUCUCAGCUCAAGUUCCUGCGGCUUCUUGACUCGUCAAACCAAGGUCAUAUUAGAUUAUCUGGUGUGGGGGGGCACUGGCUCUCAGCCCCAAGCCCUCUAGGCCAGAGAUUUUGAGCUCCUCCCAACAGGUCAAAGCUUUGUUUUUGUUGUUUCACUUCCCACCACUGUGCACACAUCUCAUCUUUGCCUCUGUUUUUAAAAAACAUUUUCUGGAGCAAAUGCUGAAAUCAGAAACCUGCAUUUCUCAUUUUUUAGUUGCCCACCAGAGCUGUUGCUCAGUGCAGGGAAACCAGGAAAUGGUGACUACCAGUCAGAAACAAAAAGACUGUCUUUUAAAUCAGCUGCUGCAGCCUUGGUAUUCCCAGCAUGGAACUUCUAAAACUUUUGGAAUUUCCUUAGCGAUAGGACUGUUUUCAUUCUGCUAAUGAGGGAACUCACUUUGUCCCCAGAUAGCUUCAGCUUGGGCUCUGAUCACCAGAAAGAUCAAUCAGAUGAAAUUGCAGGGUUUCAGGAGGCUGAGGCAGGAGAAUCACUUGAACCCGGUUGGCAGAGGUUGCCAUGAGACAAGAUCGUGCCACCGCACACUGCAGCCUGGGCAACAGAGCGAGACUCUGUCUCAAAAAAAAAAAAAAAAAGAAAGAGAAAAAGAAAUUACAGGGUUCAAACUUUUUGAACUUUGGGCUGCCCGGCAUCCAGGGAGAAGAGUGGCACUGGAGAUUAAGUUCACUCACAUGGCCAGUGAUUUAAUCAAUCAUGCCUAUCUAAUGGGAACCCUAAUAACAACUCUAGAUUCUGGGGUUCACUGGAGCUUCUGGUUCAUGAACACACUGAUGUGUUGGGAGGGUGAUACACUCAGAUUCCACAGGGAAAGAGGGUGGAACUGCAUCCCCCCUAGAUCUCACCCUGUGUGCAUCCUUUACAAUAAAACUAUAGCCAUAAAUCUAGUACUUUCCUGACUUCUGUUAGUCAUGUUAGCAAAUUAUCGAACCUGAAGGGUGUCCUAGAGUCUGGGGAUUGGUAGUUGAACAGUUAAAAGUGUGAGUGGCUUUGAGUAACUUGUGAGUAACUUGCCCAGAACCACAGAGCUAGCAAGCAGCAGAUAAUUACAUGCAAAUCCACACAGCUGGCAUGUGAAACGAGGGCAGUCUCCUGGAGGCCUGAGCCCUUAACACAUGGGGUCUACACUAACUCCCAGUAGCAAGUGUCAGAAUUAUACUGCAGUGCACCCAAUGGGAUGCAACAGAAUAACUGUUAUUAAGGAUAAUUUUGCAAUUUCUUAAUAGAAUUCUUGAAAUAUUAGAAACACCUUCUAGACCUUUAUGUUGGUCAUUACAGCUCAAAGCACUGUCCCUGGGUGGACAGGUUAGACAGAUCAUGUGGAAGGUGCUACUCAAAGUGUGGGCCCAGACUAAUGCACAUCCACAACUGUUCAUUACCAGUUCCUGGUAAGAUGUUUACAGAACUUGAGAGCAGGCAUUUAGAAACUUUUAUAGCAAUUGUACAAUGCCAAGACAUUCAGAAAUGGAAAUAUUAAAAUAUCACACAGUGACAAUUUGGGGGAAAAAUUACCCUUCACCACAGAUAGUUUGGGGAGUGUAAAUUUAGAAAAUGUAGCCUUGGUUGGUAUGACCAGAUGGAAUCAGAACUUACUGUGAAAGGUGUGAGCCAUAGGAUGAAGCAGAUGGAUUUGCAUGUAAUAUCUGCUGCUUGCUAGCUCUGUGGUCCUGGGCAAGUUACUUAAUUGCUCUGGGACUCAGUUCCCUCAUCUAGAAAAUGGAUAUGACAGUAUUUCCUAUCUAAUUCGAUGCUGGAAAGACCAAAUAAAAUAAUCCAGAACAAGUGCUAACCACAGACCUGUAUAUAUAGUAAGCUAACUGCGGGUAUUAAUUCUUCUACGCUCGCUUCUUGGCAUCCGUGGUUCCGGCUUGGUUAAAGUAUAUUCUGUCUAUGUAGGUUUGAUGUAUUACUGUAUAUAAAAUCUAUAGCCUUGCUCUCAUGUGAAUACAAAAUAAAGUAAACACAGUUUAAAAGCCACAAUUUAUACAUGUAAGCGAAUGUUGCAUUUUGUAGAAUCCCUCUGAGAUGCUAGAGUCUUAUCUGAAAAUGUUGCAGUUGUUGGAAGCAUUUUUAGGACUUCUUCUUUUUGGCUUAAUUUUUCUUUUUAAUUAUUAUGGGUAUAAGAUAGUUGUAUAUGUUACUGAUGAUUUCUGGAACUUAUUUAACAUUUCCAUUAGAACCUGUUCCAGUGAUCUUCUGAUGUAACAAAUCACCUUAAAAUGUAGGAGUUUACUCAGCAUCAUGCAAUAUGCCCCUGUAACAAACCUGCACAUGUACCCCUGAAUCUAAAAUUUAAAACAAAUACAUAUAUAGGUAUAUAAAUGUAUUUAUACACAUCUAUACACAUCUCAAACAAAACAAAUAAAAAAUAACUUCGUGGUUUAGAACAACAAUCUAUCAUUAUCACUCACCGUUGACUGACUGGGCUAGACCGGCUCUCCUAUCCGGUCUUCCAUGGGGUUGCAGUCAGAUGUUGGCUGGAGAUGGAGUCAUCGGGAAGUGCAACAGACGGGACAUCCAGAAUGACUUCUUCGCGCUUCACAUUUGGUGCCUGGGCUGGGAUGGCUGGGAUGGCUGGGACGGCUGGAACAGCUUGGGGCUGGCUGGGUAUCUCUCAUUCCACGUGGACUUUCCUAGCUUGGGCUUCCUCGAUGCAUGCUGGGCUAAGCUUAGGGAUAUGUCUUCACUGGUGUCUGGCUUCCCCCAGAGUGAAUGUCCUGAGAGGCAGAAAGUGGAAAAUGCUAGACCUGGGCCUGGUAACUGGCAUAGUAUCACCACAGCCAUAUUCUACUAGUCCAAGCAGUCAUUGAGCCUGUCCUUAUUUAAUAGGGGGAGACACAGAAUCUGCCUCUCUCUGGGUGGAGGGUCACAGAAUCUGUGUCCACCUUUAACCUGCCAUAGAGCCACAAAAGGAAUGUAGUUUUCUUAGUUUAGCACGUCCUUUCCCACCAGCGACAUUGUAUGACUUCCCAAGGUGACCACAUUGAGGUAGGAACAUUCAUUUUGAUUUCAGUUCCUAUCUUUUUUAGUGAAAACACAACCAUUGUAUUACAGCCAUGCCCUACAUGCCUUUGUGUUUUGGCAUUGGUCAGCCUGUACUGGGGAAGGAUCGUGGGGGUCACACAUUUCCCCUGGCAGACCCUCCCCUCAGAAUCACCCUACUUUCUGAGUAUCUGAUUUCUACUAACGACUUCCUUGCAGUCUGUGUUGCCUCCCUGCACUCUUCUCUACCUUACUUGCCACCAAGGAAUCUCCUGAAAGCCCAUGGAACCAAUGCAUAACUCCUUUGCUCUCAGAACUUCACUCUCUCCCUAUUUUUUAUACAGCAUGUGCCCCAGACAUCCAGGUAGGCACUCCAGACCCUCCACAGCUGGAAGAGGAUAGCUUUCCAAUUAUGUUUUCCCCAAAUGGUCUUGCUUCUUCUUCCAGCACCCCCACCAAAACACCCAUCAUAGCCACAGACACACAAGGCCCUCUGCAAAACGCACACACAAACACAAGCUCAGAUCAUUUACCCAGCCAAUAUUUAUUGAAUAUCUGCCUGUGCUUGGUUUAGUGCUCAGCUUGAAGUUCCAGCAAGCUUAGUUAUUAUUCCACAAACAUACCUUAGGUUAUUUUCCCUUUCCAGGACUUUGCUUAAGUUCCUGAAGUUAGGAGCAUUUCUUAUUAAUGUUUUUGUGUUUCCUUUGGUACUAAGUGCUGUGUGCUUCCCACACAGCAAUACAUAUUAGUUGCAAUGCUGUACAGAGGAGAGGUUCAUUCUCUUUCAUUGUAUCUUACUUUUCAUCUCUGCCCCUUUUGUUACCCUUUCUCUGAGUCUCAUCUAGAAUCAGCAAGCUCUCUCCCCAUCUCUCCUCCUAUUUCAAGUUUUAAUGUACUUCCCUCUUAUCUCACCAAAAGUUCACGGUAAGGGUGAAGUAGGAGGGUAGUCUUGGGGACAUUGUUGAAGACAACAGGCACCCUGAAAUAACAUUCACCCACAGACACAGUCACUGAAGCAUUGCUUUAUUCAGUGCCAUCGGUGGACUUCUGGUAUGUUCUAGGCAGCCUUCCAGAAUGGGGAGAACAGGAAGAAUCAGAUAGGGUUGUCACUCCUUAGAAGUGCACAGCAGCGCUGCUGUAAAAUCUAUGAGCUCUGAGCUUUCGGUGGUCUGAUAGGCAGACAAAAGGGGCAAACCAUGCUUACCUCUCUGGCUUUGCUUUAUCAAAUUGGAAUUUUAUCAUCUCAGAAGUAGGGGGAACUUGUGGGCAGGGGCACUACUGUCUAUCAAAGUGGGAAGGCAGACGUGUCCCUGAGUCACAUGGGGAGGAUUUUGCAAAUAUACACCCAUCCAUCGCCUCUCUCCAAAGACUCACCUGAGAUGGUUCAUUCUGCCACCCAUCUGCAUUAAGACACAAGGUGCUGACCGCAGAGACCUGCCAUGAAACCACACUUGAAGCAAUGGAGACAACGAAUGCUUUUCGGAAUAUUCGCUUGGGGGCUCCUCUUUUUGCUGAUUUUCAUCUACUUCACCGACAGCAACCCCGCUGAGCCUGUACCCAGCUCCCUCUCCUUCCUGGAGACCAGGAGGCUCCUGCCGGUGCAGGGGAAGCAGCGGGCCAUCAUGGGCGCCGCACAUGAGCCCUCCCCGCCUGGGGGCCUGGACGCACGCCAGGCGCUGCCCCGCGCCCACCCAGCCGGUUCCUUUCAUGCGGGGCCUGGAGACCUGCAGAAAUGGGCCCAGUCCCAAGAUGGGUUUGAACAUAAAGAGUUUUUUUCAUCCCAGGUGGGGAGAAAAUCUCAAAGUGCUUUCUACCCGGAGGAUGACGACUACUUUUUUGCUGCUGGUCAGCCAGGGUGGCACAGCCACACUCAGGGGACAUUGGGAUUCCCUUCCCCCGGGGAGCCAGGCCCACGGGAGGGGGCUUUUCCGGCUGCACAGGUCCAGAGGAGGCGGGUGAAGAAGAGGCACCGGAGGCAGAGAAGGAGCCACGUGUUGGAGGAGGGCGACGACGGCGACAGGCUGUACUCCUCCAUGUCCAGGGCCUUCCUGUACCGGCUCUGGAAGGGGAACGUCUCUUCCAAAAUGCUGAACCCGCGCCUGCAGAAGGCGAUGAAGGAUUACCUGACCGCCAACAAGCACGGGGUGCGCUUCCGCGGGAAGCGGGAGGCCGGGCUGAGCAGGGCACAGCUGCUGUGCCAGCUGCGGAGCCGCGCGCGCGUGCGGACGCUGGACGGCACCGAGGCGCCCUUUUCUGCGCUGGGCUGGCGGCGCCUGGUGCCCGCCGUGCCCCUGAGCCAGCUGCACCCCCGCGGCCUGCGCAGCUGCGCUGUCGUCAUGUCUGCAGGCGCAAUCCUCAACUCUUCCUUGGGCGAGGAAAUAGAUUCUCAUGAUGCGGUUUUGAGAUUUAACUCUGCUCCUACACGUGGUUAUGAGAAAGAUGUUGGGAAUAAAACCACCAUACGCAUCAUUAAUUCGCAGAUUCUGACCAACCCCAGCCAUCACUUCAUUGACAGUUCACUGUAUAAAGACGUCAUUUUGGUGGCCUGGGACCCUGCCCCAUAUUCCGCAAAUCUUAACCUGUGGUACAAAAAACCGGAUUACAACCUGUUCACUCCAUAUAUUCAGCAUCGUCAGAGAAACCCAAAUCAGCCAUUUUACAUUCUUCAUCCUAAAUUUAUAUGGCAGCUCUGGGAUAUUAUCCAGGAGAACACUAAAGAGAAGAUUCAACCAAACCCACCAUCUUCUGGUUUCAUUGGAAUCCUCAUAAUGAUGUCCAUGUGCAGAGAGGUGCACGUGUAUGAAUAUAUCCCAUCCGUGCGGCAGACGGAGCUGUGCCACUACCACGAGCUGUACUACGACGCAGCCUGCACCCUCGGGGCGUACCACCCACUACUCUAUGAGAAGCUCCUGGUGCAGCGCCUGAACAUGGGCACGCAGGGGGAUUUGCAUCGCAAGGGCAAGGUGGUUCUUCCCGGCUUCCAGGCGGUGCACUGCCCUGCACCAAGUCCAGUCAUUCCACACUCUUAAAAAGGGUUUCUUGGGAAUCAAUGUGCAAUAAGGUACUACUGUUGUACUCAAAGUCACAAAAGAAUACUUGAAGAUAGAUUUUAGACAGUGUAGUUUUGAGUCUUUAAACAGUAAUUUAGUGGUGGUCAUGAUAAUCCUUCUCUUUCUAAGCCAUUGAGUAUGUAUUACUGCUUUGAACAUAGAAAUGGUUUUUUUAAAAAAAUAAGGCUCAAGAAAGAUGCAAAACCAAGGAUAGCUAGAAAGAAAACACAUGUAUGACCAUGGGUAUGAUACCUCCAGAAAUGUUAACAACUUAUUCUUCUGCCAUGAGUACCCCUCAUCAGGGUUGGUUUCAAUGACAGGUUUUGGUGAUGUUCCUGACCAUAUGAAGUGGUUUAUGUUUAGAAACAUUCAAAUUGAGGGACAUCAUUUACAGCAUCGAGUGUGUCAGUUAUACAUGCAUUCAUCAUUAAAUAUCCUAGGUUUUAUGACAGACAUUGAAAUUAUCACUCAGAUGUGUUUAACAGCAAAAAAUUCCCAGCACAUCCUGGCAAAGGCUUUUAUUUCCAACCGUUGCAUUCUUCAUCUCUGCCUCCCAUUGCCCACUGAAUGCUUUGCUUUCUGUGCAUCAAGACAGAGUUCUAAAACCAGAAAACAUCCAUCUUGAAAGGUCCAAGAAAAAGCCAAAUUCCAUAUAGCACCACAGAGGAGGCCCUUUGUUUCCCUGCAGUAUUUCAACCAGGAACAUUAGUAUCACAUCCACCAGGAGGCACAUCACUGGCAAGUAACAUAGAAUCACAGGGCUGCAGGUGCCCCUGGACACUCCCCGGUUCUGGCUUUUCUGCCUUGUACCUCCUCACCUGCAGAUCUACCCUGCAGCUUUUGCAUAGUCAGUGACACACUUGACAAUUGGCACAGCUGUGCUGGGGAAGACGGGAGACACCUUGCUCCUUCCAAACUAGAAGGAAAGAUUUUGGAGCCAUCACCCUGUGCUUCUAGGGAUGCACGCCUGUCUUUAUUAUACAGGUUUCUUGCAGGUUUUUAUCAGCCAGUGGGAACUCCACAGUGAUGAGCACUGAAUCUUCACUAAAUCUUCCUACAGACAUUUAGGAAUCCAGUCCUUGCUUUUGCAGAUAUGUUUUAUGUCAGCAGCAUGACAAAGCCAUAUAAUUAAAUAAUUUAUGUGAAAGCAUUGCUUAUUAACAAGGAAAAUAUGUAGAUGCUUCAGAGGGAAAGGCAGCUAGAGGGAAAUUUUCAUCCCAAUAUGUUAGCUAUAUUCAGGGUUGAUUUUUUCUUUAAUCUCAACUGUCACUGAUACAUUGAAAAAUUUUUGCUAUGAAUAUAGUGAAACAGAAACAUUCUGUAAUACCUUAAUUAAACAUGCUAUUAUUUCAAUGUAUAACCAAAACAUAUCUCCAUGGUACAGUUAAGACUUGUUGCAAUGACAAUAGCAGCUUAAUUAAAUGCGUUCUCCCUUGCAAAAUGUAUGAAUGUCAGGAGAGUUUAGUGGAAAAGUUUUCUUUGUUUCAGGAUUGGUUUCUUCUAGACUGUUCUCAGGACUACUUUCUUGAGCAAGAAUGGCUUACAGAGACUGAAGGCUUCUGUUUGGUUAGUCUAUUCAGCAGAUAUGGAGCUGGAAAACAAGACAUCUCCUAUAGCUUGCUAUAAUAGUGAAGGAGAAAUUGGAAAGUUUUAAUCACAAUAAUAUCCAAUAAAAGCCCAUUUUGAGAGUUUUGUUAUUAAGUCAAUGAGAAGGGAUAGGUAACUUUGUCCUAUAUAUUAACUUAUGUCUAAAUAGACAUGGUUAAGCCAUGUUCCUUUCUAAUUUCUUUUCUUUUCUUUUUUUUUUUUUUUUUUGAGACAGUCUCUCGCUCUGUCGCCCAGGCUAGAGUGCAGUGGUGCGAUCUUGGUUCACUGCCAGCUCUGCCUCCCACGUUCACACCAUUCUCCUGCCUCAGCCUCCUGAGUAGCUGGGGACUACAGGCACCCGCCACCACGCCCAGCUAAUUUUUUGUAUUUUUAGUAGAGACAGGGUUUCACCGUGUUAGCCAGGGUGGUCUCGAUCUCCUGACCUUGUGAUCUGCCUGCCUCGGCCUCCCAAAGUGAUGGGAUUAUAGGCGUGAGCCACCACCGCGCCCGGUCAUUCCUUUCUAAUUUCUUGAAAAAACUUUGUCUUGUCCUUAUGUUUACAUGUGUGUAAUAAUUUCAGCAACUCUGGAAUGUGGGUGAGGUGGCUGUGGUGGAUGAAUAUUACUCCCUACCCUCCUUGGAUCUUUCUAGAUCUUCCAGACCAUUAAAUGCCCCUGAAGCUCCUUUUAUAGUUUUGCAAGUGGAUUUACUUGUAGACAUCCUUACUAUCCAGCAUAAUCCCCCUUGGCUGACAUGAGAACUUGGUUAGAGGAGAAUUUAUUGGGGUCAGUGUAAAUAUUCAAGUUCAAAAGCCUCAGAACCCAACACUUUAAAGAUUUUUAAAUGGAAUUUUGUCGUAGUCAUUGUACUUUUAAAAUAGUACUUUCAGUUUCAUUGAGGUUACAAGAAAGACUGAAGAGUACAAAGGAAAUUUAGUUACAAUUUUUGCAUUUAUUAUGGCCUUAAAGACUCUUGGGAAUCAGGCUCUGUUCAACAGUCAAUAAAUGUAAUACACACAUUAAUAUAGUACUGACUGGGCGUUCUUCUAUAAAAGUUUAAGUUCUUUGGCUUCUAAGAAAAUGUUGGGCAGUUACAGUUAACUUGAUGACUACUUCUAGUAUUAGCCAAAUGGGUCCUAAGUGGCAGCAUUUUGCCAGACAUUGACUAAAUCCUUACAUGCCACAUUUACUGAAUUCCAAUAAACAUAUAGUUCUUCUGUGGAGUAGUUAACAGUAAGUGGCAGCUCACUGAAUUUCUCCCAGGUUCUGUCUCUUCCAAAAUCCUCCAUCCUCUCUUAUGAAGGGAAGCUGAUAAAAAAAAAUCCUCUUGGUGCAAGCUGAAGCUGUUAAGGAUUCCUUUUUUCACUCUCAGGACCAACAGACGUUCUUUUGUAUUUCAAGAUAAUUUCACCUGUUGUUGUUGUUGUUGUUGUUGUUGUUGUUGUUGUUGUUGUUGUUACAAAGAAACAAAUUUUGAGCAGCAAUGACAAUUCAACCAUAUCUAGAUUCUCCCUACCUUAUUUCUCCAGCCAGUCACACCAGGCAGACGGGUAACCUUUAACAGACCUGGUGUUCUCAUGGAAUACCGAUGCUCGUCCCAGGGAGCUGACCUUUCUCACUAUGUCCUUAUAGAGCUGCUCUUACAGAGAACUUUGUGCUCAGGACCAAGGGAUGGUCAAUUAAAAGUUGCAUGUAAGCAUCAGGCUUGGAUGGGCAAGGGAGGGCUUUUAUACAUCUUUGAACGACCAGGUCUUUCCUUGUCUGCCUGAAGGCAGAGCUUCGAGAAACAGCACUUCCCAUGUGUCUGGUCCUCUUGGUCUCUCAGCCAGACACUUAAUCAAUCCUGGACUCUCCAGUAGUCCUCAGUCAUUGUAGCCAUAGCAUCUGCAAAAAAAGAAAUGCUAAAAUAAUCAUUAGCGUUUUCAAAAUUAGGAAAUCAAAGUAGCUGGGUCACUCUCUUACAUGUGUAUGAGCCAGUUAAUUCUGCUGGACAGAUCAUACUUACGCUGCUGAUUGACUCUUCUGAGCAGUAACACAUCUCCUGAAUUAAUUAGGUAGGUCCCGUUUGGGUGCUUUAAGUGGGAUCAGUCUUAGAUGAGUGCCAGUAUGUGAUUGAAUUUCAUACGCACAAAUGCCAUGAUUCAAGUUCUCUCUCCAGUUUUUCUUAUAGAUCAACACACAGUACAUGUGGUCAGUUACUUGGUUGAAUUUCUGCUUAGCUGUGGUAAGAGACAGAGAAAGGGAGUGAGGUGGGACCAGGGGAAUUAUCAGAAAGACAUGAGUGAACCUAUUGGCCAGGUAGCUUCCAAGUAUGUUCUAUUGUAUUGUCUGUUUUGAUUCUGAUAGUUUAGAACUCUUUCUGAUAGUUUAGAACUCUUACCCAGUGGUUACAUGACUGAUCAAGGCAACUCCAUCUGGAAAUUAAUUGCUUGGGUAAAAUGUCCCUGAGUUUCAACUUGUCUUUUAUCUCUGGAUAUUCUCUUAUGAGAUUAUUAUGCAUGUUUCUGUCACAUGGGCAUUAUUUACACACUUGAUAAAUGAAAGGUAUUUCUCUGUCCGUUCAAGGAAAUAAAAUGUAAGUUCUUGUUUUAUUAAAUGAAUGAAGCCUUUUGGUUAAAAAAAAAGUAAUGUAAUAUGUUUCUGUUCAAACUUGAGCUAAUGACAUUUAAGGAAUUAAAGACAUUGAUCUAGUUCUUAGUAUGAAAAGUGUACAUGUAGAUAUAGUUAUAUAAUUGUGUAUAUACAUAUCUACACACAUGGUUGGUUUUAUAUUGCUUUUUCAUCAAUAUUUUUGACUGAAACCUUUACAAUAAAUUUUAUUUUAAUUAUGUAACCACUAAUAUUUUGAGAGAAGGAAGCAAAUGUUAUAUGUCCUUCUGUUAAAAGAAAAAAAAUUCAGUCCUCCGCCAACCGCUUCCCACACACUCAUACUCUGCACAUCUUGGCUACAUUAAAAUGGACUGACAGAAUUAUUUAAAAGGCACUAUGAAGGUAGAACACUACCUUAAUAUUUUAUCCUAGUCAGAAGCCUGAUUUAACACUGAACUUUGAAGGGAAGCUUAGCUGUAGCUCAUGGCUUUCAAAGAUUAGAAGAAACAUUUACUGGUUCUAUGGAAAAUAGUCUUCUUGCUAGGUAGAUUGGAAACAAAGAAAUUGCAUUGGUGGUGUUAAAAUCUAACAUUUAUAACAAAUCCUGUUUUAUUCUAGAUGAAAUACUUAGACAAUUCUUCCAGUGGAAACCAGUGAACUUUUUUAACAGCUUUGGGAAUUCUUUUGUAUGAUAAUUUUUAAAAUGAAAUGUGUACUCUUCAAACUAAUUAAAGCUUGAAGUUUUCCAGGAGUCGCAUUUUAAAAGUGUUUGUACACAUUUUAACACUUGGAUAUUUUCUAUUUUGGUUUUGUAUAUUUUUAUGUAUACACAAUGUACAGACUUUUUUCUUGUAAAUAAAACAUGUUUUCAUUUGUCUAGAA